GGAGCCCGGCUGGCGGGUGACCCAGCGCCCGCGGCUCCGAGAGGAGCGAGGUCACCCGGCGCUUCCCGAGACCUUGGCCCUAGGCCCAGCUGGCGCUGGGACGCGAGGCAACCGAGCCGCCGGCCAAUCAGCGCUUUGCAGGACUAGCACGCAGGGGCCGCACCCCUGAGGGUGACCGGAACCGCUCCCGCGGGAAGGGCAGGGUGCGGCGCCUGGCCGCAGACAGACAAGGGGGCGCCGGCUCUUCAGAACCCCAGGGAGAAAGCGGUGGAGGGCUAGAGUUGAGGAGACUAAGGACAUUUGAGGAGGGCAGGCAUUACCAAGUUAAAACCUCCUGAAAGACAACUCCAUUGGGCGACCGUCUGCGCCGCACAGCCUGACGGGAGCGUCAUCCUUCCUGCGCAGGCUGCAACCGACAGACAGGCUCGGCUCCGCCUCCAGCCGCGGGGCACGCGGGGAGAGCCGUUCCUCCCUCCCUCCGCUAACCCGGACAGCAAAGGAGCAUUUCCGGCGUAAGACUGUCCCUACGGAAGGGGUGGGGCUAGCUUGGCCCCGUCUUUCACGCCCAGAGGGGGCGGGGUGAACCGUGACAGCGCUUCGGCCCGCACUAAGGCCGGCUCUUGUGCCGGAAGGAGGAAGGCGUGGGCAUUCGCCCCUCGGAGCUAGGGAGUGUGUGCGACGCCGCUGCGAGGUCACGUGAGCCACUGCCGGCAGAGAGGGAAAGGGGCGGGGCCCAGAACGAAGCGGGGAGGCGCCCCUUGUUUCCCUGGGGUCACGCGCAGCCGGAAGUGGCGGCUGCUGCGGAGAAUUGGAGAUGGGGACCGCCCUGGACAUCAAGAUUAAAAGAGCGAAUAAAGUUUAUCACGCCGGGGAAGUGCUCUCUGGCGUGGUGGUCAUAUCGAGUAAGGAUUCAGUCCAACACCAGGGAGUGUCUUUGACCAUGGAAGGAACUGUAAACCUCCAGCUCAGUGCCAAAAGUGUGGGUGUGUUUGAAGCUUUUUAUAAUUCUGUUAAGCCUAUCCAGAUUAUCAACAGCACCAUAGAAAUGGUGAAGCCGGGGAAAUUUCCCAGCGGCAAAACAGAAAUCCCUUUUGAAUUUCCUCUGCACUUGAAGGGUAACAAAGUUCUGUAUGAGACGUAUCAUGGCGUGUUUGUCAACAUUCAGCCUCAGAAGGGGAAGUUUACUCCCAGUCCCGUGGACUUCACGAUUACACCUGAAACCUUACAGAACGUCAAAGAGAGAGCUUUGCUUCCCAAAUUUCUCCUUCGAGGACAUCUCAACUCAACAAACUGUGUCAUCACGCAGCCACUAACGGGAGAGCUGGUGGUGGAGAGCUCGGAAGCCGCCAUCAGAAGCGUGGAGCUGCAGCUGGUGCGCGUGGAGACGUGCGGGUGUGCAGAAGGCUAUGCCCGCGACGCCACGGAGAUUCAGAACAUUCAGAUCGCCGACGGGGAUGUGUGCAGGGGCCUCUCUGUCCCCAUCUACAUGGUCUUCCCUAGGCUGUUCACCUGCCCUACACUGGAGACCACCAACUUCAAAGUGGAAUUUGAGGUUAACAUCGUGGUGCUGCUUCACCCUGACCACCUCAUCACGGAGAACUUCCCGCUGAAGCUCUGCAGGAUAUAGCCCGGAGGAGGGAAGCAUAGAGAACGGGAGUGGCCAUCUGGAAAUCCAGCUGGUUAUCCAAAUCCUAAGGGGAGCUACAGCCAGCGGCAUAUACUUGUUUUUGUGAUUAUUCUGUAUCAGAAAUGAAACAGACCCUCAAAUUAACUUUCCUUCCUCAUUUCUUGAGGCUUCUGCUUCCAACAGGCACCUCUAAUCAGACCUUUUCUUUGAAAUUCAACAAGAUUUCUUAAUGCUAUUUGCCAAGACCAUUUCACAGAAAACAUUGACUGUGGCUCUUGCCUUAUCUGUUCCUUUUUAGGUACAGUAAAACAAUUGUGACAGCAGUUUGAGCUUGCUGGAGAGUGGCAUCAUGGGGACAAAAGGAAACCUCUGACUUGCUAAUGGAUGUAGCCAGGGACUCCCCAUAGCAAAGGGUCUGUGGCCAGUUGACAUCCAGGAUGGCUGCAAGCGCACUUGAUGGUCAGGAAGUUUGCAGAUACUCGCCAAGGCAGAGCGCAAAGUGCUAGCCACUGGAAAUGCAUGACUUCCCUCCACCCCUACUCUAUUCUGUAGUUUUUUGGUUUUGUUUCUGAGACGGAGUCUCAGUCUGUCACCCAGGCUGGAGUGAUCUCAGCUCACUGCAACCUCCACCUCCCAGGUUCAAGCGACUCUCCUGCCUCAGCCUCCCGAGUAGUUGGGAUUACAGGUGACUGCCACCGUGCCCGGCUAAUGUUUGUAUUUUUAGUAGAGACGGGGCUUCACCAUCUUGGCCAGGCUGGUCUUGAACUCCUGACCUCGUGACCCACCCGCCUUGGCCUCCCAAAGUGCUGGGAUUACAGGUGUGAGCCACCACACCCAGCCUCUGUAGUUCUUUUUACAACAUUUUUCAUUAUAACUUUAAAUUUUUUAAGCAACUGGAAAAGUGUUCCUUGCUCUCUUGGGGGGAUUUGGCUGGUGCCGAAGUGUUUCUGAAGUCUCAAGAACUGCCAUAAAAUCUCACGCUGCCAUUUCCCUGAACAGAUACAUACAUAGAGAGAGACAGUUUUCCAAACUGUGUCACGCAGGCUGAGUGCACUGGCAGGAUCACAGCUCACGGCAGCCUCAACCUCCCUGGCUCAAGCGAUCCCUCCCCUCAGCCUCCUGAGUAGCUGAGACUACAGGUGAGUGCCACCACACUCAGCUAAUUUUCAAAUUUUUUGUAGACAGGGUCUCCCUAUGUUGCCCAGGCUGGUCUUGAACUCCUAGACUCAAGUGAUCCUCCUGUCUUGGCCUCCCAAAGUGCUGAGAUUACAGGUGUGAGCCACUGUGCCCAGCAGUUUCCCAGAAUAUAUUUAAAUGCAAAGUUACAUGAGGGGAAAACAUGUAUGUUUGCUCCUGUUGUUACUGGGUAGGUUCUGAACAGCAGAAACCCAUGUGCAGGGUGGGCUGGUGAAGGCCCCUCUCCGCAAGGUGGUAGCAGGAAAAGGUCCUUGACUUGAUGAAUUUGGUCUGCCUCUGAGCCACUGGAGGAAGCUGUUUUGAGCCAGGGUUUUUUGGCCUAAAGCCAGCAUUUCCUCAGUCUCCCUUUGUGGUUCGAAGGAUAUGGACUAUUGCAAUACAUUUCUUCCUUCAAAUCCUGCCACUGUUUUGUUGGCCCACAACUAAUAGGACCUCAAAAUAAGCCAUGCUGCUUUGCACACACACUAGCCUUCUUUUGUACUUUUCAUUCUGGAUGGGCUUGGCCAAAACAGGCUCAGGCCAAAGACCUCCCAAGCUGUAUGUACUUCCAGUAUCCUGAAACAGUGUUUGGUGACAUAAUGCCAAGGGUAAACAAGCCUGAUUUAGGCACUGCUUUAUCCAGGGGCUUCACCCAUGAAAUUAAUAAAACUUAUCUGAGUCACUUGAAACUUGGUUCCCAGAAAACACAUUUCUGGUUUAUAAUCUCCUUUUAUGCUCACCUGACAUUAAUUAUCUAUCCUUGAUGAUGUGUUUAAACUGAGUAGCAGAAAACAGAGGCCACACUUUCUGGGAAAUUUUAAAGGAAGAAACCAUUUUUAAUGAGAUGAAAAUAUUUAACGAAUUUAAAAAGCUAAUGACAAUUUUGAGAAAAGGUUUGGGAUGUAUAUUGCUAUGUAAUUUAAUAAACUGAUUUUAUGGAUAUAAAUA